ACCCCGGCGGCGGCUGGAGAGCGAGGAGGAGCGGGUGGCCCCGCGCUGCGCCCGCCCUCGCCUCACCUGGCGCAGGUAGGUGUGGCCGCGUCCCCUACCCGGCCGGGACUUUCUGGUAAGGAGAGGAGGUUACGGGGAACGACGCGCUGCUUUCAUGCCCUUUCUUGUUCUACCUUCAUCGGCCGAGGUAAAAGUGCUGAAACCAUGUGAAUAAAAUACAGCUUGUUUGUGACCACUGAGGCCCUUGGUGAAUAUCUUAGAAGUCACUCAAAAUGGAUAAAGAAUGAAUGUGAGUCACCCAUAGCAGUCUUAUGUGAGAUAAUAUAUGGUUGAUCCUCAGUAUUCAUGGCUUCUGAAUUUGUGAAUUUGCCUACUCACAAUCACAGUCAUUUAUCUGUAAUCCCCAAAUCAAUAACCAUGAUGCUUUCAAGACCAUUUGAGGUCAUACACACAGUGUAUUAGUUCAUUUUCCCACUGCUGAUAAAGACAUGCCCAAGACUGGGAAGAAAAAGAGGUUUAAUUGGAAUUACAGUUCCACAUGGCUGGGGAGGCCUCAGAAUCAUGGCAGGAGGUGAAAGGCACUUCUUACAUGGUGGCAGCAAGAGAAAAUGAGGAAGAAGCAGAAGAGGAAACCCCUGAUAAAUCCAUGAGAUCUUGUAAGACUUAAUCACUAUUACAAGAAUAGCAUGGAAAAGACUGGCCCCCAUGAUUCAAUUACCCCCCUUCCUUGGGUCCCUCCCAUAACAUGUGGGAAUUCUGGGAGGUACAAUUCAAGUUGAGAUUUGGGUGGGGACACAGCCAAAUCAUAUCACCCACCCCUGGCCCCUUCAAAUCUCAUGUCCUCAAAUUUCAAAACCAAUCAUGCCUUCCCAAUAGUCCCCCAAAGUCUUAACUCAUUUCAGCAUUAACCCAAAAGUCCACAGUCCAAGUUUCAUCUGAGACAAGGCAAGUCCCUUCCAUCUCUGAGCCUGUAAAAUCAAAAGCAAGCUAGUUACUUCCUAGAUACAAUGGGGGUACAGGUAUUGGGUAAAUACACCCAUUCCAACUGGGAGAAAUUGUCCAAAACAAAGAGGUUACAGGGCCAAUGCAAGCUGAAAUCCAGCAGUGCAGUCAAUUUUUAAGCUCCAAGAUGAUCUCCUUUGACUCCAGGUCACACAGCCAGGUCCCAUUGAUGCAAGAGAUGGGUUCCCAUGGUCUUGGACAGCUUCAUCCCUGUGGCUUUGCAGUGUACAGCCUCCCUCAUGGCUGCUUUCACAGGUUGGCAUUGAGUGUCUGUGGCUUUUCCAGGCACAUGGUGCAAGCUGUCAGUGGAUCUACCAUUCUGAGGUCUGUAGGAUGGUGACCCUCUACUCACGGCUCCACUAGGCAGUGCCCCAGUAGGGACUCUGUGUGGGAGCUGUGACCCCACAUUUCCCUUCUGUGCUGUCCUAGCAGAGGUUAUCCAUGAGGGCCCUGCCCCUGCAGCGAACUUUUGCCUGGUCAUCCAGGCAUUUUCAUACAUCUUCUGAAGUCUAGGCAGAGGUUCCCAAACCUCAAUUCUUGACUUCUGUGCACUCGCAGGCUCAACACCACGUGGAAGCUGCCAAAGCUUGGGGCUUUCACCCUCUGAAGCCACAGCCUGAGCUCUACGGUGGCCCCUUUCAGCCACAGCUGGAGCAGCUGGGACACAGGGCACCAAGUCCCUAGGCUGCACACUGCAUGAGGACCCUGGGCCCAGGCCACGAAACCACUUUUUCCUCCUGGGCCUCCAGGUCUGUGAUAGGAGGGACUGCUGUGGAGGUCUCUGACAUGGCCUGGAGACAUCUUCCCCAUGGUCUUGGGGAUUAACAUUAGGCUCAUUGCUACUUAUGCAAAUUUCUGCAGCUGAGUUGAAUUUCUCCCCAGAAAAUGGAUAUUUCUUUUCUAUUACAUAGUCAGGCUGCAAAUUUUCCAAACUUUUAUGCUCUUUUUUUUUUUUUAAUAAAACUGAAUGACUUUAACAGUCCCCAAGUCACCUCUUGAAUGCUUUGCCUGCUUAGAAAUUUCUUCUGCCAGAUACCCUAAAUCAUCGCUCUCAAGUUCAAAGUUUCACAGAUCUCUAGGGCAGGGGCAAAAUGCUACCAAUCUCUUUGCUAAAACAUAACAAGAGUCACCUUUACUCCAGUUCCUAACAAGUUUCUCAUCUCCAUCUGAGACUGCCUCAGCCUGGACCUUAUUGUUAAUAUCGUUAUUAGCAUUUUUGUCAAAACCAUUCAACAAGUCUCUAGGAGGUUCCAAACUUUCCCACAUUUUCCUGUCUUCUUCUGAACCCUCCAAACUGUUCCAGCCUCUGCCUGUUACCCAGUUCCAAAGUCACUUCCACAUUUUGGAGUAUCUUUUCAGCAACACCCCACUCUUCUGGUACCAAUUUACUGUAUUUGUUUAUUUUCACAUUGCUGAUAAAGACAUAUCUAAGACUGGGAAGAAAAAGAGACAGUUCCACAUGGCUGGGAGGCCCCAGAAUCAUGGAGGGAGGUGAAAGGCACUUCUUAUAUGGCAGCAGCAAGAGAAAAUGAGGAAGAAGCAAAAGUGGAAACCCCUGAUAAACCCAUUAGAUCUCAUGAGACUUAUUCACUACCAUGAGAAUAGCAUGGGAAAGACUGGCCCCAGUAAUUCAAUUACCUCCCCGUGGGUCCCUCUCACAACAUGUGGGAAUUCUGGGAGAUACAAUUCAAGUUGAGAUUUGGGUGAGGACACAGCCAAACCAUAUCACAGAGUGGCACAAAAUUUUAGCCACAUGCAUAUUCCAGACGCUCCAACUCCUCCUUUCACCUCAUAUUAUAAGUAAGUGUCUUUUUCCCCAGUCUACUUAGUGCCGUAUUUUUUGCAUUUUUGUUCCUUUUUUCAAAUUGUGGUGACUUUGCUGUUUAGAGUACCCCCAGCUGAAGUGCUAUCUGGUGUCCCUAGGUGUAAGAAGGCUGUGCUGUGCCUUACAGGGAAAAUAUGUGGGUUAGAGAAGCCUCUGUCAGGCAUGAGUCAUAGUUAGUGCUGUCGGCCGUGAGUCCAAUGGUAGUGCAUCAACAAUAGAUAUGAAAUAAGGUGCCUUUACACAGAAACACAUAAAACAAGUGAUGCAUUGAUCAGUUGAUGAAAAUAUGGUGACGGCAGGCUCUCAGGCACAUAACCCCUGAGAAGCGAUGGGCUACUACUUGCUAAUUCAGUUUUGGGGGUGACUUUGUGGAAUGUAUAACCUGAAAUAAUGAGAAUAAACUAUAUUCUACUUCUUUUACAAAGCAAGGAAAUAAUUUUUAAAAGCAAGUUAAAUUUUACUGUUUUUGUAAGAGAUAUGUUUUCGAAACAGUUGAACUGUUUUAUAACACAGAGAAAGUCUCUUUGCCUUACAUUUUAUAUUAGUUAAUUAAGUCAGCAGAUUUUUCUUGGGCUCCUGUGAUGUGACUGGCACUGUUUUGGUACCAAAAGGGCAUUGCAAAAAAAGUCCAGAAGUAGACAGAUCACAGCCUUCAGGAUUAAAAGCAGUCUCAUCAAUGUGAUAUUUCGUUUAAACUUAGUAGCAAGCCCAUUGAAUUCUCAAAAUGAGAAUCUGCUAAUUAUCACACACUUUUCUUAUGAAAGAAUAAUUUUUCAUAGUCAAUAUUUCUAAAAUAUAAUGUCUCUUUCUCAUUAGCAGAGACCGAUUGUAUGGCAGAUUUACUUGCACCUGCGGAUGCUGGAGAUAGGUGAUGAUUUAGUAUAGUGCACAUCCACCAGGCGGUCCUCCUGGGUCCCAAUAUUUAGGCCCACAGGAUGAGUCCAGGUGAUAUUGGGCACAGGCUCACUCAGAGGCUAUCAGACAGAAAGCUCUGCCUCACUGCACAGCAGCUUCAAGCAUUGCCUUCAGUGGGAGUCUUACUUGCAGUCCACACAGCUCAGGUACAAGGCCCCUGAGGUCCACACCUGGAGCUAAUCAUCUCUUUGAAUAACACUGUAGACAUAGCUACCAGAAAAUAAAAGAAAUAGAAAGGCAUGAUUAAUACAAGCCUCACUAGGUUCUUAUUGUGAAGAUCUGAGAAAGAGCUCCUCAUGGCCCUGGCAUGGGAGGGAAGAGUGAUAACUGUAAAAUACCCCUAGGCUUUCUCCAUGACAAUGGUUACUCUCCAAGGGAAAACACUUUGCAAGAGCCUUGUCUCAGCUGGGAAUUCCCAAGGGAAUUCCUCAAGUUCCAGCACCCUCAUCACUUUAUCACUUAAAGGACAAAAAACUCAUAGUCAACAGGGGUCAGCGCUUCAAGGAAAUUGUUACAGAAUGGUAAAGGGGUCGAAUAUCCAAGAAGACAUAACAAUCCUAAAUGUGUAUGUGCAUAACAACAGAGCAUCAAAAUAUGCAAGACAAACACUGGUAAGACUGAAAGGAGAAGUAGACAAAUCCUGUCUUAUAGUUAGAGAUUUUAAUCUCUUUCUCACAAAAGUUGAUAGACCAAAUAGAUAGGAUAAAAAUGACCUAAGCAGUACUGUCACUCAACUUGAUCUAAUUGACAUUUAUAAAAUAUUCCAUUCAACAACAGAAAAAUACACAUUCUUCUCAAGCUCACUUGGAAUAUUCACCAAGAUAGAGCACAUUCUUGGAAAACAUGUUAACACAUUUGAAAGACUAAACGUCAUACCAAUUAUGUUCUCAGAACACAGUAUAAUUAAACUAGAUAUCAACAACAAAAAGAUGGAGGUUUUGGGAAAUUUCCCAAAUAUCUGGAAAUCAAACAACAGACUUCUAUAUAACCUAUGUUUCCAAGAAGAAGUCUCCAAAAUCUAAAAAAAUAUUUUGAAGUGCAUAAAAAUAAAAAUAUAAUUUAUCAAAAAUUUUGGAAUGUAGCAAAAGCAGUGCUUAUAGAGAAAUUUAUAGAACUAAGUGCACACAUUAGGUAAAAAAUAUAUAAAGAAAAUUACUUGUGAUUCUACUUUUAAGAAACUACAGAAAGAAGAGCAAAUUAGGCCUAAACCAAGCAAAAGAAAAGAAAUAAUUAAAAUGAAAGCAGAAAUCAUUGAAAUUAAAAACAGGAAAACAGUAGAGAAAAGUCAAUAAAACCAAUGUUGGUUCUUUGAAAUCAUCAACCAAAUUGAUAAACCUUUAACCAAGAAAAAAAAAAGAAAAAAAUGUAGAAGAUGCAAUUUACCAAUAUCAGAAAUGAAGGAAAGGUCAUAACUGUUGAUCUAAUGGAUAUAAAAAGAUGAUAAAGGAAGAUCAUGAACAACUCUGUACUCACAAAUGUGGUAACUUAGGUGAAAUAAACUAAUGCUUGAGUGACACAAACUACUAAAACUUACAGAAGAAAUAGGUAGCCUGAAUAGCCCUAUAUCUUUAAAAUUUAAAUUAAUAUAACCUUUAAAACAGAAAUCAUCAGGCCCAGAUGGGUCCACUAGUGAAUUCUGUCAAACACUUAAGAAAGAAAGAAUACCAGUUUUCCAUAAUCUCUUCCAGAAAAUAGAAAUGGAGGAAACAGUUUCUAAUUCAUUUUAUGAGUUCAGAUUUCACGUAAUACCAAAACCAGUUAAGGCAUUACAAGAAAACAAAGCAAUAUUACUUAUAUAUACAAAAACCCUCAACAAAAUGUUAGAAAAUCAAACCCAACAACGUAUGAAAAGAGCUAUGUACCACAGCCAAGUGGAAUUUAUUCCAGGUAUGCAAAACAGGUUCAACAUUUGAAAAUAAAUUAAUGUGAUACAUCACAUCAAUGGGCUAGAGAAGAAAAAUCAUAUGACCAUGUUAAUGGAGGCAGAAAGGGCAUUUGACAAACUCAAAACACUCUUUCAUGUCAAAAAAAAAAUCUUAAACUAGGAAUAGAGGAAAACUUUUGUAACUUGAUAAAGAGCAUUAAAAAAAAAAACCUACAGGUAACAUCAUACUUAAUGGUGAGAGACUGAACACUGUCCCUCUGAUACUGAAAACAAGGUAAGACUGUCCUCUCUUACCACUCUGUUCAACAUCCUACUGGGAGCCCUAGCUAGUGCAAGAAAACAAAACAAAACUUAUACAGAUCAGAAAAGAAGAAAUAAGACAUCUUUUUUCACAGAUAAUAUGCAUGUCCAUAUGGAGAACUUCAAAGAAUCCAUAAAACAACUCUAAUAACCAAUAAGUGAGUCUACAGGAUGCUAGAUCAAUAUACAAAAGUCGGUUGCUUUCCUAUAUACCAGUAGUUAACUAUUGAAAUUUGAAAUAAGAAUAAUUACCAUGUAUAAUAGCACCAAAAAGACAAAAAAAAAAAAACACAAGAAAAUACUUAGGUAUAAAUCUAACAAAAUAUGUACAGGAUCUGUAUGCAGAAAACUACAAAAUAAUGAUGGAAGAAUCAAAGAAGAUGUAAGUAAAUGGAAAAGUAGUCCAUGUUCGUACAUUGGAAGACUCAAUGUUGUUAAAAUGUUCAUUCUGCCAAGCUUGAUCUGUAGAUUCAACCCAAUCCCAAUCAAAAUCCCAGCAAGCUGUUUUGUAGCUAAUGAUGAAAUGAUUCUGAACUUUACUUGGGAAGGUAAAAGAUCUAGAAUACCCAACACAAUACCCACUAAAAAGGACAAAGUUGGAGGACUCACACUACUCAAUUUCAAGUCUUACUAGAAACAGAUACAAUUUCUGCCCUUAUGGGACAAACAGACAUUCAUCAAAAAUUCACAUGCUAGAAAGUAAAGGUAAAUUAAGUCAAAACAGUGGUCAGUGGUACAAAAGGAAAGCAUGUUAGUUUUGACUGUGGGGACAGGGACAUGUUUAUCCUGAGCUCAAAGGGUAGCCUGGACAGUGGAGGAUUUUUAGCAGAGAAAAGGGCCACAGCUUAGAACAUGUAGGAAGGGAGCAAGGUGGGGGCACUGACAGCCAGAGCUACUCAAAAGAGAUGUGGAGGAAAAGGAUGUUAUGUGGUUUUGGAGACAAGUAGGCAUGUGUGGGAGGCUGAGACGUGAGAUGGGAGGGAUUGGCAAGGGGUUGACUUUCAGCAGUGUAGAGAAGGGAAUGAUCUAAGAGAGCUUGGAUUUUCAUCUUCAUAAAUGGAUGGAGCUCUUGGGCCAAGGUUCUCAAACUUGAGCCUUUAAAAUACAAAACCUAGAGCUUCACCCCAGAGUUUCUGAUUUGGCAGGUCAGGGUGGAACCCUAAGAAUUUUCAUAUCCUCCAUGUUUCCUGGUGAUGCUGACAUUGCUGGUCCAGAGACGCACAUUGAGAACCCAGCUCCAGGGAACAAGAAGGAGCUCCAAGUUAGGCAGGAAAGCCCCAAGCUUACAUUUGGAUGGGUUGACUAUGAGGGCCUUUGCACUGCCACCUGAAGAUGGUAGCUAAGAGAAGAGGCAGGCUUCAAAUAUUGGCUCCACCACAUACUGUGUGUUCUUCAGCAAGCCAGUUGACCCUCCUGAGGCUCGAUGACCAGGUCUGUGAAUUGAGGAUAACAAUAGUAUCUACCAUUAGGGAUGUUGUGCACAUCAGUUGAUAACCUUUGAGUCAAGUACUCAUGGAAUAGCUGUUUUGCAUUAUCCUCAUCACCUUCAUCAUCAUGGCCAUUCUGGCCAGCACUAAAGAUGUACAGCCAACCUCUUCUGUGGCUGAAGUUUAUCUUCUAUAAAAUGAGAACUUGUUUUUCAUGAAGCUGUCAUUUUCACAAGUUUGGGGUGCAGGUGCAGAUUGCCUACUGUUGUGUUUCUGAACACUUCCCUCGCGAGGCUCCUAACCCCACCCCAGUAAACUCAUCAACAUGACUCCUUCCAGCUUCUACAGCUCUGGAGAGGGUUCCUUUUUAUCUUGCGUUUCCAGGGAUGUUUCACGGCCUUUUGUGGAGUGGGCCCUGGCUGAGCUUCUGGCCCUUCUUGAGUGUGGAGGAUGUCACAGACUGCAGUGGGAAAUUAAAAAGCUGCUUGCUUCACAGAGUAAGGGAAUGUUAGUAGAUGCUUGAAAAGUACCCUGAGGGAGCUGGUCAGAGGUGCUCUGUAAAGUUGCAUCUGUUGCUAGCACCAUGAGCAGCUGUCUGACCAGGAGGCCUGGGAACAGGGACAGAGAGAGCUGGCACCCUUCUUUCCUCUGCCCUACACAUUGGCCUUUCCGCCAUUAAGACCAUCUCUGCUUGACUUUUUCAGUCUCCUGGCUGGCAAUUAGCAUCUUGAGGUCUCCAUUAAGAUCUUUUCAAGGAUGCUCUUCCUAUUUGGUUCAAUCUUCUGGUUGAAUUUGAUACAUGUUAUGAUGUAGGACUUUUUAAAAAAACAUAAAACAAUCAGGAAAACCUCGCUAUACCCAUUCCAGCAAUUCAAGACCAAGUUCAUUUUUGGUAAAAACACUUGGGAAAGGGCAUUUCCAGGCUGGCUAAGCACUAAAUGGCACAGCCCUGUCCACUGACUCCCUCCUCAACUGGUGUGUGUUCUGGAGGGAUCCAUGUCUCAGAGCAUUACUUCAUUUUGAAUGUGCAAUUAAAAGAGGCCCCGUGCUGCUGGGGAUCUCACACUUCUGCUUUCUGGUUUGUUUUGCAUGCUGACACUUUGAGGAAAAGCCCAUUUCCCUAAUUACAGACAUCGUCCAGCAGCAGGAAGCACUCUGGCUUGUUGAUGCCUGUCUUGUGCUUUCUCUCUGUUUCAGCUGUUUUCCUUUUAAGAUACUCCUCUCAGAUUUGUGUGCUUCUUCCCUUCCCACAUUCUAUACUGCCCAGCGCCUGGGAUUCCAGAUCUGCGUUUGAAUCCAGGAAAGGGAGGUGGACACCUGCGCAGGUGUGUGCCCUCCGGCCCCUGAAGCAUGGCCAGCAGCGGCAUGGCUGACAGCGCCAACCACCUGCCCUUCUUUUUCGGCAACAUCACCCGGGAGGAGGCAGAAGAUUACCUGGUCCAGGGGGGCAUGAGUGAUGGGCUUUAUUUGCUGCGCCAGAGCCGCAACUACCUGGGUGGCUUCGCCCUGUCCGUGGCCCACGGGAGGAAGGCACACCACUACACCAUCGAGCGGGAGCUGAAUGGCACCUACGCCAUCGCCGGUGGCAGGACCCAUGCCAGCCCCGCCGACCUCUGCCACUACCACUCCCAGGAGUCUGAUGGCCUGGUCUGCCUCCUCAAGAAGCCCUUCAACCGGCCCCAAGGGGUGCAGCCCAAGACUGGGCCCUUUGAGGAUUUGAAGGAAAACCUCAUCAGGGAAUAUGUGAAGCAGACAUGGAACCUGCAGGGUCAGGCUCUGGAGCAGGCCAUCAUCAGUCAGAAGCCUCAGCUGGAGAAGCUGAUCGCUACCACAGCCCAUGAAAAAAUGCCUUGGUUCCAUGGAAAAAUCUCUCGGGAAGAAUCUGAGCAAAUUGUCCUGAUAGGAUCAAAGACAAAUGGAAAGUUCCUGAUCCGAGCCAGAGACAACAACGGCUCCUACGCCCUGUGCCUGCUGCACGAAGGGAAGGUGCUGCACUAUCGCAUCGACAAAGACAAGACAGGGAAGCUCUCCAUCCCCGAGGGAAAGAAGUUCGACACGCUCUGGCAGCUAGUCGAGCAUUAUUCUUAUAAAGCAGAUGGUUUGUUAAGAGUUCUUACUGUCCCAUGUCAAAAAAUCGGCACACAGGGAAAUGUUAAUUUUGGAGGCCGUCCACAACUUCCAGGUUCCCAUCCUGCGACUUGGUCAGCGGGUGGAAUAAUCUCAAGAAUCAAAUCAUACUCCUUCCCAAAGCCUGGCCACAGAAAGUCCUCCCCUGCCCAAGGGAACCGGCAAGAGAGUACUGUGUCAUUCAAUCCGUAUGAGCCAGAACUUGCACCCUGGGCUGCAGACAAAGGCCCCCAGAGAGAAGCCCUACCCAUGGACACAGAGGUGUACGAGAGCCCCUACGCGGACCCCGAGGAGAUCAGGCCCAAGGAGGUUUACCUGGACCGAAAGCUGCUGACGCUGGAAGACAAAGAACUGGGCUCUGGUAAUUUUGGAACUGUGAAAAAGGGCUACUACCAAAUGAAAAAAGUUGUGAAAACCGUGGCUGUGAAAAUACUGAAAAACGAGGCCAAUGACCCCGCUCUUAAAGAUGAGUUAUUAGCAGAAGCAAAUGUCAUGCAGCAGCUGGACAACCCGUACAUCGUGCGGAUGAUCGGGAUAUGCGAGGCCGAGUCCUGGAUGCUGGUUAUGGAGAUGGCAGAACUUGGUCCCCUCAAUAAGUAUUUGCAGCAGAACAGACAUGUCAAGGAUAAGAACAUCAUAGAACUGGUUCAUCAGGUUUCCAUGGGCAUGAAGUACUUGGAGGAGAGCAAUUUUGUGCACAGAGAUCUGGCUGCAAGAAAUGUGUUGCUAGUUACCCAACAUUACGCCAAGAUCAGUGAUUUCGGACUUUCCAAAGCACUGCGUGCUGAUGAAAACUACUACAAGGCCCAGACCCAUGGAAAGUGGCCUGUCAAGUGGUACGCUCCGGAAUGCAUCAACUACUACAAGUUCUCCAGCAAAAGCGAUGUCUGGAGCUUUGGAGUGUUGAUGUGGGAAGCAUUCUCCUAUGGGCAGAAGCCAUAUCGAGGGAUGAAAGGAAGUGAAGUCACCGCUAUGUUAGAGAAAGGAGAGCGGAUGGGGUGCCCUGCAGGGUGUCCAAGAGAGAUGUACGAUCUCAUGAAUCUGUGCUGGACAUACGAUGUGGAAAACAGGCCCGGAUUCGCAGCAGUGGAACUGCGGCUGCGCAAUUACUACUAUGACGUGGUGAACUAACCGCUCCCGCACCUGUCGGUGGCUGCCUUUGAUCACAGGAGCAAUCACAGGAAAAUGUAUCCAGAGGAAUUGAUUGUCAGCCACCUCCCUCUGCCAGUCGGGAGAGCCAGGCUUGGAUGGAACAUGCCCACAACUUGUCACCCAAAGCCUGUCCCAGGACUCACCCUCCACAAAGCAAAGGCAGUCCCGGGAGAAAAGACGGAUGGCAGGAUCCAAGGGGCUAGCUGGAUUUGUUUGUUUUCUUGUCUGUGUGAUUUUCAUACAGGUUAUUUUUACGAUCUGUUUCCAAAUCCCUUUCAUGUCUUUCCACUUCUCUGGGUCCCGGGGUGCAUUUGUUACUCAUCGGGCCCAGGGACAUUGCAGAGUGGCCUAGAGCACUCUCACCCCAAGCGGCCUUUUCCAAAUGCCCAAGGAUGCCUUAGCAUGUGACUCCUGAAGGGAAGGCAAAGGCAGAGGAAUUUGGCUGCUUCUACGGCCAUGAGACUGAUCCCUGGCCACUGAAAAGCUUUCCUGACAAUAAAAAUGUUUUGAGGCUUUAAAAAGAAAAUCAAGUUUGACCAGUGCAGUUUCUAAGCAUGUAGCCAGUUAAGGAAAGAAAGAAAGAAAAAAAAAAAAGGCCUGGAUACUGCUUUUGCUGUCUCUGUUAUGAGAUGGAAGACUUACAUGUUUGUGAUAAAAGGGGACCAUGAGAAUGAAUUGGCUUGGCUUACUUUCCCCCUGAAAUCCUCUCUCCUGCAGACUGUCUUGAAGACCUGGUGACUGGUAAAUAAAGCCCUGCAUGGAGGCUGCACAGCAGGGGCAAGAGGCCCAUCCCCCAGCAUCUCACUGAGGACAGCUUCAGGCUGCCUUCCUCUGAACGUGGUCCACACCUUCCUCUCCUCCACAGAGAGGGUGCCGCCAGAAUCCCCUGUCGCUUUCUGUGUCUGCAAUGGGGGGCAGCACAGGGAUCAAAGCCAUCUAAAGAGUUUCCAAAGAAAGUAUUAAUUCAGAACAAGCCAAAGACCCUGAGCCUCACCACAAACAGGCCUUUUGGAGUGUGAAUUUGAGUUGAAGAUACAAGAUCGGAGAAUGAUUUUCUGGUCUUAACUAAUCCUCAUCUUCAUGUUUGAUCUUUAAGAAGUCAUCACCCAUUGAUUUCAGUUUUGCUGUACCUCUUGAAAGUUAAAGAGACAUCUCAGCACUUUAGGAGGCCGAGGCGGGUGGAUCACUUGAGGUAAGGAGUUUGAGACUAGCCUGGCCAAUAUGGUAAAACCCCAUCUCUACUAAAAAUACAAAAAUUAGCCGGGCAUGGUGGCAUGUGUCUGUAGUCCCAGCUACUCGGGAGGCUGAGGCAGGAGAAUCGCUUGAACCCAGGAAACGGAGGUCGCAGUGAGCCAAGAUCAUGCCACUGCACUCCAGCUUGGGCAUCACAGCGAGACUCUGUCAAAACAAACAAACAAAAAAACAACUUAAAGAGGUAAUUUAGCCAUCAUUCUUAUGCCAGCAGAUAUAAAUAAACUUGGACCCAUCUGGUCUUCAGCUAAACCUGAGACAUUUUAAAGUGCAUGGACAGCCAUGGACAGCAGGCCCUCCUCUAACAGGGGAUGCAAGGCAUGGAGAAAGACAAUCAGUACCCAAGCUCAGCCACAGAAGACAGGAGUCACUCAUAUAACUUGUGUUUAGAAGUUUUUGGUAGCCACGCACACUUUCUGAAAUCACACUAUCUGGUGGUUUAAUCAUAUUUUUAAAGACAGAAUCCCUGAGUGCUGAGCAGAUUCUCAAAACACAUUUAGAAUCCCUGAAAUUAGAAAGAUCAAUGACAAAAUAUCUGUCAGCCAGGCCACAAACAGGUGUAAAAUUAUGAAAGGAGUGGUUGGAUGUGCCAAGUUUGGUAAAGUGGUGACUGCAUCUGAGAAAGAGGCUGUGAGGCUGAACUCUUGGUGGCUUCCUUCUGUAACUUCCAGAGGGAGUCUUCAACACAGGCCCCGUGCUCGUAGGAAUACGGUAGCACCUAUGUAGGAAGUGCGUGGAGUUUUCUGUCUUCUUUCUGUGUGAUUUUUGGCCUUUUUAUCAGCACUUCUCCCCUCCCAGGAGCCUGGGGAUGCCAAACAUCCAGAAUGUGAUGGGACAAGAUGGGGGCAGGGGCCUCACCUCCCUGCAGAGGUCCGGCCAGGUCUCCUUGUCCCUGGACAAUCUCCUGAGCCUCUCUGCUUGGUGGAGCAGGCACCUGUGUGCAGAAUUCCCACUGUGGCCAGCACGAGGAAGUCUUUUCUAGUGAAAAUGUGUCUUGUGGUCAGGAAUAAUUAUCCUUUCCCCUGUAGCCACCAAGGAGGGCAAAUAGAGAAAGGUAACCUAAUUGAAGGAUUGGUCAUGUGAAAAGGGCUACAUUUGGGAAGCUGGGAAAGGCCUCCAGGCUUCUAGAGCAGCUAGCUUGGGCUGGAUUCUCAUACCCAGGCUGCCCCUUGGAUUGUUCUACCCAAGCUUUUCCCUGGGGUCUGGGCUCACUCCAUAAGGUAAGGUGCCUUUUACCUUAUGGUCCUUCUUUAGCAGGUAACAAAGGAGCAUCAGGGGCAGGCUGCCCUGGUGGCAUCACACUGGCUAGUGAGGCCGUGAAUAUCUUGUCCCCCAGCAGGGCCGACAGUUUCUAUCACAGAAAACAGUGUGUUCAGUGGUGAAAAUCGUUGCAUGCAUGUUUUCAUCUGAGCGUGUCCUUCUCCCAUACUCCCUAUCAGCCAGCCCUGCCUGUAGCUGCUGUAUGGUGAUUGCACUUGGACAUCAGUCCAAUGACUGCAAGUCGGCCUGGAUUUUCACUUGCAGAGGCUACAGCUGCAUUGUCAGGUCUCCCAGCCCUGCAGAGAGCUCCCUCCACUGGUUAGCAGUGUGUUGUGUUUUCCAUUCAUUUCAGAAGAGCUACAUUGUGUCACUGGACAUUUUUAAAAACUGUGAUUUUUAAUAAAAAUUUAAAAUUUG